CGUGACCCUCAGGUGACGCACCAGGGCCGGCUGCCGUCGGGGACAGGGCUUUCCAUAGCCAUGGCCCAGCAGUGGAGCCUCCAAAGGCUCGCAGGCCGCCAUCCGCAGGACAGCUAUGAGGACAGCACCCAGUCCAGCAUCUUCACCUACACCAACAGCAACUCCACCAGAGGCCCCUUCGAAGGCCCGAAUUACCACAUCGCUCCCAGAUGGGUGUACCACCUCACCAGUGUCUGGAUGAUCUUUGUGGUCAUUGCAUCCGUCUUCACAAAUGGGCUUGUGCUGGCGGCCACCAUGAAGUUCAAGAAGCUGCGCCACCCGCUGAACUGGAUCCUGGUGAACCUGGCGGUCGCUGACCUGGCAGAGACCGUCAUCGCCAGCACUAUCAGCGUUGUGAACCAGGUCUAUGGCUACUUCGUGCUGGGCCACCCUAUGUGUGUCCUGGAGGGCUACACCGUCUCCCUGUGUGGGAUCACAGGUCUCUGGUCUCUGGCCAUCAUUUCCUGGGAGAGAUGGAUGGUGGUCUGCAAGCCCUUUGGCAAUGUGAGAUUUGAUGCCAAGCUGGCCAUCGUGGGCAUUGCCUUCUCCUGGAUCUGGGCUGCUGUGUGGACAGCCCCGCCCAUCUUUGGUUGGAGCAGGUACUGGCCCCACGGCCUGAAGACUUCAUGCGGCCCAGACGUGUUCAGCGGCAGCUCGUACCCCGGGGUGCAGUCUUACAUGAUUGUCCUCAUGGUCACCUGCUGCAUCACCCCACUCAGCAUCAUCGUGCUCUGCUACCUCCAAGUGUGGCUGGCCAUCCGAGCGGUGGCAAAGCAGCAGAAAGAGUCUGAAUCCACCCAGAAGGCAGAGAAGGAAGUGACGCGCAUGGUGGUGGUGAUGGUCCUGGCAUUCUGCUUCUGCUGGGGACCCUACGCCUUCUUCGCAUGCUUUGCUGCUGCCAACCCUGGCUACCCCUUCCACCCUUUGAUGGCUGCCCUGCCGGCCUUCUUUGCCAAAAGUGCCACUAUCUACAACCCCGUUAUCUAUGUCUUUAUGAACCGGCAGUUUCGAAACUGCAUCUUGCAGCUUUUCGGGAAGAAGGUUGACGAUGGCUCUGAACUCUCCAGCGCCUCCAAAACGGAGGUCUCAUCUGUGUCCUCGGUAUCGCCUGCAUGAGGUCUGCCUCCUACCCAUCCCGCCCACCGGGGCUUUGGCCACCUCUCCUUUCCCCCUCCUUCUCCAUCCCUGUAAAAUAAAUGUAAUUUAUCUUUGCCAAAACCAA